AGUUGGUCCUUAGUACUGCGGCCGUGUGGGUGAGUUGGCUGCCGGUGAGUUGGGUGCCGGUGGAGUCGUGUUGGUCCUCAGAAUCCCCGCGUAGCCGCUGCCUCCUCCUACCCUCGCCAUGUUUCUUACCCGGUCUGAGUACGACAGGGGCGUGAAUACUUUUUCUCCCGAAGGAAGAUUAUUUCAAGUGGAAUAUGCCAUUGAGGCUAUCAAGCUUGGUUCUACAGCCAUUGGGAUCCAGACAUCAGAGGGUGUGUGCCUAGCUGUGGAGAAGAGAAUUACUUCCCCACUGAUGGAGCCCAGCAGCAUUGAGAAAAUUGUAGAGAUUGAUGCUCACAUAGGUUGUGCCAUGAGUGGGCUAAUUGCUGAUGCUAAGACUUUAAUUGAUAAAGCCAGAGUGGAGACACAGAACCACUGGUUCACCUACAAUGAGACAAUGACAGUGGAGAGUGUGACCCAAGCUGUGUCCAAUCUGGCUUUGCAGUUUGGAGAAGAAGAUGCAGAUCCAGGUGCCAUGUCUCGUCCCUUUGGAGUAGCAUUAUUAUUUGGAGGAGUUGAUGAGAAAGGACCCCAGCUGUUUCAUAUGGACCCAUCUGGGACCUUUGUACAGUGUGAUGCUCGAGCAAUUGGCUCUGCUUCAGAGGGUGCCCAGAGCUCCUUGCAAGAAGUUUACCACAAGUCUAUGACUUUGAAAGAAGCCAUCAAGUCUUCACUCAUCAUCCUCAAACAAGUAAUGGAGGAGAAGCUGAAUGCAACAAACAUUGAGCUAGCCACAGUGCAGCCUGGCCAGAAUUUCCACAUGUUCACAAAGGAAGAACUUGAAGAGGUUAUCAAGGACAUUUAAGGAAUCCUGAUCCUCAGAACUUCUCUGGGACAAUUUCAGUUCUAAUAAUGUCCUUAAAUUUUAUUUCCAGCUCCUGUUCCUUGGAAAAUCUCCAUUGUAUGUGCAUUUUUUAAAUGAUGUCUGUACAUAAAGGCAGUUCUGAAAUAAAGAAAAUUUUAAAAUAUUUGUUAAUAGACUGUUCUCUUCUAAUAGUCUUUUUUUUUUUUUUUUUUUUAAGAGAUGAGGUCUCACUAUAUUGCCCAGGCUGGUUUCAAACUCCUGGGUUCAAGUGAUCUUCCCGCCUCUGCCUCCUGAAGUGCUAGGAUUAUAGGCGAGAGCCACUGUGCCCAGCCAUUGUAAUACAGUCUUUUGUUUGAAAUGCAAAUGUUAGUGGGCCAAAAGGACAGUGUUAUUAAUAUCCCUAUUCUAUGAAGAUGUCUGUUCUAAAACUGUUUUAGUGAUGCUCUAUAACAGAAUCAACUAUAUCCAUUAAUCCCAUGGUGUUGAUAAAUGAACUAGUCCAGCUCUUCCCAGUGGUUAAUAGAUGUUAACAGCACUGUAAAUCCAUUUCGGCCCUAUAAUUUCUGGAGCAAACGUGUAUUUUUGCUGCUUUUCUUAUAAGGAGAUGCUACUAAUUGACUAUCAGAAGAACAUGUUUUGAGGUCCUCCUCAAAACAUUGAUGGGUUGGAAUCAGCCAUCAACAGUGUUGUACCAGUUCUUGGGUCUUGAUAGACAAUUUGGAAAGAGAUUUCCUUGUUUACGAAGUGAAGGACUAAGAAUUAAAUUAAUGACCUUGGCCUCACUGGCAAUCAAUUACAAAUCUCUAUAUCAGUAAGAGAAUUGUAAAAUUCAGAAGCAGUUUACAUUAGACUUUGGAAUGAAUGAUGAACUUUCCCCAUUAGAGCUGCCAUCAUAUGAUUGGUGGAGAUUGUUUAAAGAAUCAUUCUAUCUCAGCCUCAAAAAUUACCACGGGAAGAUGGUAUCAGUAUCACUACUUAACAGAUGAAGAAUCUAAUGCUGUGUGCCCAUGGACACACAAAAUUAAGCUGUUGGGACUUGAACAGCUCAAAUUUUCUUGUUUCAGAUCACCAGCUCUUGAGUAAUAGGGAAAUCUGGAGAUUUGAAAAGUACUUGCACUGUCCACAACAUGGCUAAUCCAUAUGUGGAUGAUGCAGAAUUGAUUUAAUUCACUAACAGGGACCCCAUAAUUAUUUGCUGGGCUCUGGGUAUAUUGAUGUGUAGGAAGUUGUACUAUAUGUUAAUAAAUUAUGACUAUUUGGAUAGGCUGAAUUCAUACUAAAUCCAUACUGUAGUUCAACAAAAAACAACAUGUUUAUAUACAUUUGGAAACUGCAAUGAUAGGAAACAUUUGGAAGAAAGGGAUUUUGCCCUAGAAUAACACAUAAGGAAAGCAGAGAAUUAGAGUAUAUUGUUACUGAAUGUUCCAGAGACUUCUAGUGAUUUUAACACUUAUUAAGUAUAGCAUGUUGAUGGGGAGAUUUGUUUCUCUAAAGAUCACUUUGUUUUAUUAAAUCCUAAUAGAAAAUACCCUUGAAAAUCCUAUCUCAUUUAUUCCUGUAACAAAUUUAUUGAGCACCUACCUACUAUAUGCCAAGAAAUGUAUUAGCCAUCAGGCAGAGAGCUGUUCAAAUGGUAGAUAUGAUCUGUGCUCCUGUGAAACUUCUAGUGGGGAGAGCCAAACAAUAAACAAUAUUCCUUUUUAACUCUAGGUUAAUGCAGAAAUGGAUAAAGCCCAUGUUGCUUUUGGGAGAGGUGAGUUGUGUCUCUGAAUCACAUGCAUUUCAUAGGGGGAAAAAUGCCCAAAUACUAAGGAGUAGCUCUUAGCCUAUGUCCGUUCGCCUCAGCUUAAGUUGUUUUCCCUCCCACUGGCUGGGCAGCAUAUUUGUGUUUUACCUGGUAAAACAGUAAAUUUCGUACCUUCUAUAAUUGGCAUUCUUCAAAGAGGUAGAACUUUGAUUUUUUUGUAGAAUAUUAAAACAAGCUUUCUUAGGUUAAAGAAGUGAUCUUACUACGAACAGCAAUGGUUUCAUGAUGUGUAAUUGCUUUAUGUUAUCUUUCUGCUAUAGAAUGUUUCCUGGAGAAAGGUACGGUUUUUAGUAAUAAGAUAAAUUUACUUUAGUCCUGCAAAUAAGGUGAAAUCUUAUGUCCAGUAUCUCACAAAGGAGAACUGACAGUGCCACUUUUAUAUUUAAUGUCAAUCUCAUUAGACAAAAAUGAAAUAUAGUUCCUAGGGUUUCCAAUUUAAAAAGUGAAAUAAUAAAUAUAUUCACUCAAACAUUUUCUCAGUGCCAUAUGCAAGUUACCAUGUCCCAGAAGCUGAUACAGUUUGAAGAAGGAAAUAUAUAAGUACUGUAAGCCUGUGAUAACUAAAAGCAACAUACUAAAAAGUGAAGGUACAGAUAAUUGGAACAAAUUUAAUAGCGUUUAAAAGUGUAUUUGGUAAUUUCUCCAGGAGGUGGCACUGUUGAGUUGUUUUUUCUUUUCAGACAGUAAGACAAUAGACCAUUCAUCUUUGUGUCACCCAAACAAAGAAAUAUUCCUUUAUAACCCCCUUUCCUCCCCCCACCUAAUCACAUGCUACUGGAACUGACUGUCUUGUGAUCUACUCCCAUAGUUGGCAUAGAUUUAAAAAUAAUCUUUUUUAAAUUAAUCUGAUAGUAGUUAUGGAAAGGAACAAAUUGUUCACCAAUUUUCAUCAGCUUUAUCUUUUCAGUCCAGUAACUGAGAACUUAAAAAGACUAUUCUAGUGAUUUUACUAUCCUGCUCAGAUGGCAUUCAAAAACAUUUUUCACUUCUCACGUCUUGGAAAAAUUUGUAAAUUCGUUAAGUCUUUUUGUUUGAAAGUUAAUGUGACUGGAAAUAUUUUAAUGUAAAUAUCGGGUUGGGUGCAUUGUAUCAUUUUGCUCUACAAUGACUAUAUCCUCAUUUGGGUUUAUGGCCAGUUUAUAAUUAAAAGUAAUCUUUACUUGC